UAACUAAUCAUUUAUUUUUUAAUUUUCCAAUCUUUGCUUCUUUUAAACAGCUCUGGGAUAAAUACCCUUGUAGCAGUAUUUUUGUACAGAGGGUAGAUGUAGUGGUUAAGAACAUAGCUCUGAAGUCAGACUUCUUGGGUUCAAAUCCUGGCUUUGCCACUAACUAGCUAUAUGACUUUGCAUUGAUACUUACUCUCUAUGUUUCAGUUUCCCUUAUCUCAGAACUAGAGAUAAUAAUAGUAUCUACCUCAUAGGGUUGUUAUGAGGAUUAAAUUACUUAAUAUAUGAACAUAGUAAGAACAGUGCCAGGUACAUAGUAAGUGCUCAGUAAAUAUUAGCUAUUAUUAUGUUACCAGUAUAAAAUCCUUAGACAUGAAGAUUAUUAGAAUAUUUUUGAUCAGUAUAUCUUCAGGAAUGUUACUAUGCAUCAUUUUGUGUUACAAGACAAAAACUCUACCAUUAAUUAGUGAAAAUAUGAGAUUUUCUCUACUUUUAAAAUUUCUUUCCUAAAGAUACAAACAUUGUAAGAUAGCACUUAGUAAUCAGUGAGCCUGCUGCUGAUUUUAGGCUUGAUGCUUGGCACUGGCAGAAACAAGUCACAUAUGUCAGCCACCAGUAGUGCUGGUCUUAUGUAGGAAUCCCCAGGGUUGCCAUCUCACCAACACUAGUCCCCAACAUCUUGGUAAUUGAGUGUGUAGAGGGAAUGACCUUCAAGAAAUUUAUGGUAACUUUUCAUGCCUUGAAUCGUGGUUUAAUUUGCUUCGAAUGGCUUUUAUUUUUUUUAACAUUUCAGGGUUGAACAUUCUGAUGAGUCAGUGAUUCAGUGAUUCACAAGCUUGCUGUUCUGUCUUCAAAUAUUAUGCAUUUCCAGAUGUUAUUUAUUGUGUAAGGUGAUUUUAAACCAGUAUAUUUCAGGACAGUCAUAUAGAAAAAUACAUACCCUACCUGGAUCUGCCUCAUUAAGAAAUACUACCAAAAUCAGUGAGAAGAGUAUUACUGUUUUUGAAAAUGAAGUGUCUAACUUAAAAAAAAAAAGGCAUUCAAUUUUUCAGGCCAUAAAACAAGAGUAUAGACACGUUCAUGUGUAUAAACAUUAACCCUAACUGAGAUCGAUUUUAAGAAUACUGAGAAGAUCCUUAAGGAUCUCAUUUUGAAAAUCACUUGCUAUAUACGUCAGUAACUCUUGCUUUGGUUUAGUGGAGUUCAGGGAAUAGCUUCAUUAAUGUCUACAAACUUGUUUUAUGGACCUUGAAAUUACAGCCUUUAAUUCCCAUUAAAAAAAAAUGUCUCUAAGUUUUGAGUGAUGUUAGAAAACAAAUAAAAAAUUAUUACCACCCCAGUUUAAGAGCUCAAUAAUUAAGUAAGACUAUUUUGAUUAUAAAUGGUAGCAGUGGCAACUUGGUAGUUUUUAUUGUUGACAAUUGAAUACGUAAGUUAAAUAAUGGGGCUCCUCAGCAGAAUAAGGUUUGUAAAAGAGGACUUUUCAGCAGUUGAAGUAGAUUGAAGUUUUUAUUUGGCCUUUUUUUUCAUUCUUUUACUUGCAACCAGCUUUUUAAAAAAGAAUCUUUGACUUGAAUCCUUAAAUGCUGGCUUGAACUGUUAUUUUGUGUAAUUUUUUACUUGCCUCAAUCUUGUCCUUUCUAACCAUGUUUUGUGACUAAUCCUCUGUGAGGGAGUGUCUGGGUAAAGCUUUUGGGCCUUAAGUAACAUAACUAGGCUACAUGCAUGAGUCACAACUGACCUAAAUAUAAUCCCCAGGAAAUGAUUAGUUUGCCAGGUUUCUCCUCUAAGGGUUAGUUAGUGCUGUUUCUUAAAAGACUAAGAGAAAUUAGAAAGAUAAAUAUAUUUGUAGUCACUAUCAGAAAGUGAAUAAGAAAAAUGAACACGGCAAAUUUAGCUUCUUAUGGAUCUUUCCACUUGGUAGUUGAUUUGGCUGUCUUUUGAACUUUAACAUGAAGUUCAAAUGAGAUAUGGGUAGUAUUUUAAAAAUUUAAGCCUGUUUACUUUUCUACCCAGCUAAUAUUCUUUGCUUACUUUCCUCUGCUUUUUUCAUACUUUUUACUCUCCAGAACUGCCUAAAGUUACAGAAGAAUCUGUUCCAAGUGGAGAAAAUCAGAGUGUGACAGGAGGUGAUGAAGAAGUAGUAGAUGAAUACCAAGAGUUAAAUGCAAGAGAAGAACAGGAUAUCGAAAUAAUGAUGGAAGGCUGUGAAUAUGCAAUCUCGAAUGCGGAAGCCUUUGCAGAAAAAUUGUCCAGAGAGCUGCAGGUGCUAGAUGGGGCUAACAUCCAGUCAAUCAUGGCAUCUGAAAAACAAGUCAACAUCCUGAUGAAAUUGCUAGAUGAGGCUCUAAAGGAGGUAGAUCAGAUUGAAUUGAAACUGAGCAGUUAUGAGGAAAUGCUCCAAAGUGUAAAAGAACAAAUGGAUCAGAUCUCUGAAAGCAACCACCUAAUUCAUCUUAGUAACACUAAUAAUGUAAAACUCCUAUCUGAGAUAGAGUUCCUUGUGAACCACAUGGACUUGGCCAAAGGUCAUAUAAAGGCCCUUCAGGAAGGAGAUCUUGCUUCUUCCAGAGGCAUUGAGGCCUGCACCAAUGCUGCUGAUGCCCUUCUGCAGUGCAUGAAUGUAGCUCUUCGACCAGGCCAUGACUUGCUUCUGGCAGUCAAACAGCAACAGCAGCGAUUCAGUGAUUUGCGAGAGCUUUUUGCCCGGAGACUGGCCAGUCACCUCAACAAUGUUUUUGUUCAACAGUUUACUCAGGCCCUCCUUCAACUCUAUAACAGGUCCUACUUUCUUUCGGUUCCUGGUCAUGAUCAGAGUUCGACUCUUGCCCAACACUCUGUUGAACUGACUUUACCCAAUCAUCAUCCAUUUCAUAGAGAUUUGCUCCGAUAUGCCAAGCUGAUGGAGUGGCUAAAGAGUACAGAUUAUGGAAAAUAUGAAGGACUAACAAAGAAUUACAUGGAUUAUUUAUCCCGACUAUAUGAAAGAGAAAUCAAAGAUUUCUUUGAAGUUGCAAAGAUCAAGAUGACUGGCACAACUAAAGAAAGCAAGAAGUUUGCUACACUGCCUCGAAAAGAAAGUGCUGUCAAACAGGAAACAGAGAGUCUUCAUGGAAGUUCGGGGAAAUUAACUGGAUCUACUUCUAGUCUAAAUAAGCUCAGUGUUCAGAGUUCAGGGAAUCGCAGAUCUCAGUCAUCUUCCCUGUUGGAUAUGGGAAACAUGUCUGCCUCUGAUCUCGAUGUUGCUGACAGGACCAAAUUUGAUAAGAUCUUUGAACAGGUACUAAGUGAACUGGAGCCCCUAUGUCUGGCAGAACAGGACUUCAUAAGUAAAUUUUUCAAACUACAGCAACAUCAAAGUAUGCCUGGAACUAUGGCUGAAGCAGAGGACCUGGAUGGAGGAACAUUAUCACGGCAACAUAAUUGUGGCACACCACUGCCUGUUUCAUCUGAGAAAGAUAUGAUCCGCCAAAUGAUGAUUAAAAUAUUUCGCUGCAUUGAGCCAGAGCUGAACAACCUAAUUGCAUUAGGAGACAAAAUUGAUAGCUUUAACUCUCUUUAUAUGUUAGUCAAAAUGAGUCAUCAUGUGUGGACUGCACAAAAUGUGGACCCUGCUUCUUUCCUAAGUACUACAUUGGGAAAUGUUUUGGUGACUGUCAAAAGGAACUUUGACAAAUGCAUUAGUAACCAAAUAAGGCAAAUGGAAGAAGUAAAGAUCUCAAAAAAGAGUAAAGUUGGAAUUCUUCCAUUUGUUGCUGAAUUUGAAGAAUUUGCUGGACUUGCAGAAUCAAUCUUCAAAAAUGCUGAGCGUCGUGGAGACCUGGAUAAAGCAUACACCAAACUUAUCAGAGGAGUAUUUGUUAAUGUGGAGAAAGUAGCAAAUGAAAGCCAGAAGACCCCCAGGGAUGUGGUUAUGAUGGAAAACUUUCACCAUAUUUUUGCAACUCUUUCUCGAUUGAAAAUCUCAUGUCUAGAAGCAGAAAAAAAAGAAGCCAAACAAAAAUACACAGAUCACCUUCAGUCUUAUGUCAUUUACUCUUUAGGACAACCUCUUGAAAAACUAAAUCAUUUCUUUGAAGGUGUUGAAGCUCGCGUGGCACAGGGCAUAAGGGAGGAGGAAGUAAGUUACCAACUUGCAUUUAACAAACAAGAACUUCGUAAAGUCAUUAAGGAGUACCCUGGAAAGGAAGUAAAAAAAGGUCUAGAUAACCUCUACAAGAAAGUUGAUAAACAUUUAUGUGAAGAAGAGAACUUACUUCAGGUGGUGUGGCACUCCAUGCAAGAUGAAUUUAUACGCCAGUAUAAGCACUUUGAAGGUUUGAUAGCUCGCUGUUAUCCUGGAUCUGGUGUUACAAUGGAAUUCACUAUUCAGGACAUUCUGGAUUAUUGUUCCAGCAUUGCACAGUCCCACUAAACCUUGUGAAAGAAGAAAAGAUAACUGAAUGAAGCAUUUGAGUAUAACAGACACUAUACCAAAAUACCAAGCAACUGUUUUGAGAACCCAGACUUAAAAUUUUAUGUAUUAUUAAAUGUUAGAUAAAUGGGUAGUACCAUACUACAAAUAUUUAAAUGCAAAAUUACCAACCUAUAUAGCAGUUUUAUUUGCCCUAUAGGUUGCAUACUAACUUAAGCAUUCAUGUCACCAUAAAAUGCCUUUAGCAUUUCUCAAUGACUGGAUGGGAAAUUUUCCUUUAUUGCCUAGCUGCUUGUGUUUGAGUGGUUGUCCUAUGAGCAAUGCAUUUGGAGUUCUUCAGCUUUCACUACUUCUCUGUUGCUUGCUAAUCAUGUAACUACUAAAAUACUGUACAAAAUUGUUUUUUCACACUAACAAAUGUGUAUAUGGAGAAGAGGGCUCAUGUGAUGAUCAUUUGUGAACUUAGAUUUUUGAGGAUUAUGUGACUAGUAAUAAAUGUGAAAUAAAUUUUCAAAAAAGUUGACAUUUGAUAAUAUUUUUAGGUCUAUCAUAUGCUGUCUUCUGUAUUAAAGCAAGUUCUUACAAAAUCCA